AGUCUCGCUCCUGCCCAGCCCGGGCGGCUGCCCUUGGGUGCUCCCUUCCCUGCCCGACACCCAGACCGACCUUGACCGCCCACCUGGCAGGAGCAGGACAGGACGGCCGGACGCGGCCAUGGCCGAGCUCCCGGGGCCCUUUCUCUGCGGGGCCCUGCUAGGCUUCCUGUGCCUGAGUGGGCUGGCCGUGGAGGUGAAGGUACCCACAGAGCCGCUGAGCACGCCCCUGGGGAAGACAGCCGAGCUGACCUGCACCUACAGCACGUCGGUGGGAGACAGCUUCGCCCUGGAGUGGAGCUUUGUGCAGCCUGGGAAACCCAUCUCUGAGUCCCAUCCAAUCCUGUACUUCACCAAUGGCCAUCUGUAUCCAACUGGUUCUAAGUCAAAGCGGGUCAGCCUGCUUCAGAACCCCCCCACAGUGGGGGUGGCCACACUGAAACUGACUGACGUCCACCCCUCAGAUACUGGAACCUACCUCUGCCAAGUCAACAACCCACCAGAUUUCUACACCAAUGGGUUGGGGCUAAUCAACCUUACUGUGCUGGUUCCCCCCAGUAAUCCCUUAUGCAGUCAGAGUGGACAAACCUCUGUGGGAGGCUCUACUGCACUGAGAUGCAGCUCUUCCGAGGGGGCUCCUAAGCCAGUGUACAACUGGGUGCGUCUUGGAACUUUUCCUACACCUUCUCCUGGCAGCAUGGUUCAAGAUGAGGUGUCUGGCCAGCUCAUUCUCACCAACCUCUCCCUGACCUCCUCGGGCACCUACCGCUGUGUGGCCACCAACCAGAUGGGCAGUGCAUCCUGUGAGCUGACCCUCUCUGUGACCGAACCCUCCCAAGGCCGAGUGGCCGGAGCUCUGAUUGGGGUGCUCCUGGGCGUGCUGUUGCUGUCAGUUGCUGCGUUCUGCCUGGUCAGGUUCCAGAAAGAGAGGGGGAAGAAGCCCAAGGAGACAUAUGGGGGUAGUGACCUUCGGUGAGCAGGAGGGCUGGGGGGUGGCGCAAGGAGGGAGGAAAGGGCUUGAGUUAAAAGCGGGUGCCUGCAACCCUCAAACUCCGACAUCAUUCAGUGUGUUUAGGGGCAGGAGGUGUUGUUCAGCCGUGGAAUUUGCUGGUGGCAGCAGUGUAACCUGUGUAUUUGAGGGUACAGGCAAGCGGUACAGGGUGGAGUGGCUGGUCCACAAGCUGUGGCAGGGAAGCUGUUUGCAGGACUGCCCUGCCCCUCCUCAUAUUUAAUAAAGUUUACUUUUCUGUUCCGAA